AAGCGGGGAGGAGCGACCGCUACAAUGGAUCCUCCCGCAGGCUUUGUGCGCGCUGGGAAUCCAGCUGUCGCCGCCCCGCAGAGCCCCCUGUCCCCGGAGGGCGCUCAUUUCCGGGCCGCCCACCACCCGCGUAGCACCGGCAGCCGCUGUCCCGGCAGUCUCCAGCCGUCCCGCCCGCUUGUGGCCAACUGGCUCCAGUCACUCCCCGAAAUGCCAGUCGACUUCACUGGGUACUGGAAGAUGUUGGUCAACGAGAAUUUCGAGGAGUACCUGCGCGCCCUCGACGUCAAUGUGGCCUUGCGCAAAAUCGCCAACUUGCUGAAGCCAGACAAAGAGAUCGUGCAGGACGGUGACCAUAUGAUCAUCCGCACGCUGAGCACUUUUAGGAACUACAUCAUGGACUUCCAGGUUGGGAAGGAGUUUGAGGAGGAUCUGACAGGCAUAGAUGACCGCAAGUGCAUGAGUGAAACUGGCUUUUCCUCUUGAAUGUGCUGACUUUUGAUUCCAGCCCCCCAGGAAUGGAUCAGAGAAGAGGAGCCGCUACCCACCCACUCAUCAGCCUGGCCUCAGGGGCAGCUCAUGGACUUUUUAGCCAGAGAGAACCGGGUUCAAGUUAUGGCUCAAGCCCUAACCCCUUGGUGAUGGGCUGGUUACUUAUAGAAGCCUAAUUUUUAUCAGCUCUAAAGCUUGAAGAUUUAGUGAAACAUUGUGGAAAGCUCCCAGCACAGUACCUGGCACCUGGCAGGUUCUCUGUCAUCUCCCCUACUUUUCCCUCCUGAUCACUUAUUUAACACAAGCACCAGAUGCUGAAAACCCUCUAAUUGUCCCAGGAACACACAUACCCUCAAAGGGAGAAGCACACUUUCAAAUCAAACUCCAGGAUUUGCAUCUUUUAGCAAUUUCCAUUAUGCGGAGAAAGUAUCUACUCACUGUCUGGUUUUGAAAUUUUACCCCAAAUCGAAAGAGCAUGGGUUUUGGUGUCAGACCUGGGUCGGUCCUGGCUCUGGCCUUUGCAGGCAGUAUCACCACGGGCAAGGCUUCACCUCUCAUAACCUGGCUGUGGAACCACAGAAACAACAGAAUUCAGUCCCAGCCCUCCAGAGGUGGAUCCGUAAACAGAGGGACUACUAGGGCUGGGUGGAGGGCUGUGAGUGAUCCAACAUCCCCUGCUCUUGAGAGUGGUGUUUUAGCAUGGGAGUGUUAAUGAAUGUCACAAGUUUCUUGAUACCAAAUAGAGUUCCUACCAUUUGCAGGUCAUACCGGUCACUGCCAAGAGAUGGCUUAUUUAGUGGGAAUUGUCUGGCACUCCUAGUAUAAGUCACCUAAGUGGGGCAAGUGGGCCUUGAAACAUCCCUGGGAGACACUCACUCAGGCUGCCUGUGGGAGCUGGGCUUUUUGUGUCACUCUCCCAUGCAGCAGUGACGGCUGGGGUUUCUAAGUGGUCAGAGGAGCUGGAAAAUGGCUUCUGAAGUAACAGUCCCUUGUCAUAGUGGUACAAAGAUGUCUUCAUUCAUCUGUUGGCACAUGUCUCUGGGUAAACUGCCGGCAAGGCCAAAGUGAUGGGGGUUAUUAUUAGUUUUUAAUAGAAAAGUUAGACUGGCUUCACUUUCCAACCAGCUUCCCUAGUUCCAGCCCAUUUGCAGACUUUUGGGUGGUCUGUGGGAUGAAAAUUUCUUGUGAGGAGGUGAGCUGAAGAUGGCCAUCCCUCCUGGUUGCUCUUGGAUUGUCUGGGCUUCAUUUCUAAGGCGGUCCCAGAGCCCAUGUGGGGGUUGGGGGAAGCAGCAUUGUCUAGCCCCUUUGGUUUGUACCCAUGUUCACCCCACCCCCACAGCCACCUGCCUUUUCUGUGGGACUUGAAAAGCAUCAGGAAUAUCUUCCUACCUGAAAUUCUUCCAUUAGACCCUGAUUAAUUGGAUUAAUCUAGGAAACCAGAUUAAAUGACCAUUUAACGACC